CUUUGAAUUCUAUUUCUGGAAUUUAAUAAAUUUCUUUGUCAUUGGAAUCUGUUGCUGGUGAAUUGUUUUGCUUCUUCCAAGUUUUUGAAUUUGCUUUUAUAGACAGUGACUUUUUCUCAAAGAUGUACCUAUGAUAUUGGUUGGGUUGGCAUGUUGGCAUUGAUUCUUGGCACUUGUAGUAUUGUAGUCUCUGUAUAAUUCCUUUGGCUAUAAACAGUAUCACUGGUCUCUGAUUUCCUCAGUGACUUAGGAUAUGGUUGUUGUUGGAGACUGUGGAUCCUGGCAGUUGUAGCAGUGAGCUGGGUGAGUGGCUGGGUCCUUGGACCCCUGGGUAGUUAGUGUCACCUGUGUGAUGGCAGUAGCAGUAGUAGAACAACCCUCUGGCUCCAAAGCAUUCUGCAUUGUUGUUGGUGGCUGUAUUAGGCUGGGUGAGUUGGUCCCCUGUGCCACAGGUGUUGCAUGCAGGUGGAAGCUAGCUGUGGUAGUAGUAGUACGUUGGGUGGGCUCAUCUUUAGGUCUCUGGGAGAGUAUUCAGGUGCCAAUGGUGGUAGAUUGGUCACAGCCAUUCUUAGUACCCUGGAUUGUAUGCUUAGGCAUAGGGGUGGAGUCUGGCAGGGCGGGCCUAUCCUCAGGCCUCCUGGUGGUGUAUGCAAGUGGUAGGCAGUAGUAGAGUGAACCAAGCCACCUAGUGGAAUGCCCAGGUGGUGGUGGCAGUGGCUGUGAUGUGGCCCAGCUGCGGGGGAGAGUGGGGUUGCUUUUACUGGCAGCAGUCGUAGACAAUUGGCUGGGGAGCAUGCACUUUGGCUCCAGGUAGUGGCUGCAGGUGGGGUAGCGUUUCCUCGGGGCACUUGAAAAUCCAUGGUGGCUCUGCUGCUGUGAAUACCAGGGUUCUGCCAGUGGCUCAUGGUUUGGCCUCAGCAGUGCAAUGGAAGUUGCUGUGAGUGAGGGAGUCUGUAUUUAGGGCUCGUGAAAAUACACAGCAGUCCCACUGCUGGGAGUAUUGUAGUUAUUGCCAGUGGCUUACAUUUUGGCUCUGACAACAGCAGUUAGCACUCGUGGUGUCUGUGGGUAGGGGACAUCAGAGAGGUUGCAAGGAUGUGGAGACAGGAGCUGUUGAUCCCCAUGGCAGGAUGCGGUCUAGUAGAGUCUGGGAUCUCAGGAUAGUGAUGUGCAAGUUGCUUAAGACUUGGGGGUGUGUGGAACCCAGCAUGAAUUUCCUCUUUGGAGCAAUGCCAUCAUGUGAUUUCCAAGUAGUUCCUCUGUCAGUCGCAUGGUCCUAAAGGGUUGAGGCGCUCUCCUAUGGCUAGGAUUGCAGGAGUCCUUGAUAGUAAUGUGGACCACUUGGGGUGUUUCUCUUGCCCUUUACCCACGCUGAAGAGCCUCUCCAGGCUCCCAGCUGAUUCUGGCUGAGCAGGCUGCCCUGAUUUCCUCUCCUUCCUUGCCUUAGGUGUUCCUUGUCACUUCUUGUUGAAUUCAGUGUUCUCUCUUACAUGAUCUAUUCUAACUAUGAUUGUCAACUUGUUAUUUUGGUUCUUCUUUAUGGAGGAGGCAAGUACCAGAUGCCUACAGGCAUUCUUCUGUGCCUCCGACUUCAUAUUUUUUUUGAUGCUACUCUUAUUAUAAAUGGUCUACCCCAGAUCCAGACACACACAGGUGUCUUAUAAUGGUCUACCUACCCCAGGUCCAGACACACACAGGGUAGACACUGGGCAGAUGUUUCUUUGAAGAACAAGUAAAUGAAUAAAAUAUGUAAGUGGAAAGUAUUAAUGUAAUAAUGGGUCAUGUCUGCUCAUUUUCAGGAUUCUUUUCUCAGAAUUCUACAAACAUGGAAGUGGGGGUAGAGAAAGCAAAUGGAUAAUGUAAUGCAGGGUUGAGAAUUGGUGGGAAAAUGAGUGGUUUUGAACCUCAGGAAAAGGCUAGGUAGAGAGGUGAGAUAGGGAUGUGGGAAAGAGCAAAGAUCAAUAACUAAUCAAAAAGCAGUUUUUUUUUGUUUUUUUCUGACAGACUUGAGCCAUACUUCUAAUUCUGUGGGAGCUGGCACUUUUCAGUUUGUAUUAGUCCAUUCUUACACUGCUAUAAAGAAAUACCUGAGACUGGGUAAUUUAUAAAUAAAAGAGGUAUAAAUGGCUCAUGAUUCUCUACAGGAUAUACAGGAAGCAUGGCUGCGGAGGCCUCAGGCAAAUUACAAACAUGGUGGAAAGCAAAGGAGAAGCAGGCAUGUCUUACAUGAGUGGAGCAGGAGGCAGAGGGCUGGGGGCAGCUACACACUUUUUACACAACCAAGUCAAGUGAGAACUGUAUCACGAGAAGAGUACCAAAGGGGGAAAUCCACCUCUGUGAUCCAAUCACUUUCCACCAGACCCCACUUCCAAAACUGGGGAUUAUAAUUUGACAUGAGAUUUGGGCAGAGACACAAAUCCAAACCAUAUUAUUCUGUCCCUGGCCCCUCCCAAGUCUCAGGUACUCACAUUCCAAAAUUCAGUCAUCCUUCUCAACAGUCCUCAGAGUCUUAACUCAUUCCAGCAUUAACUUACAAGUCCACAGUCCAAAAUCUCAUCUGAGACAAGGCAAGUCCCUUCUGCCUAUAAGCCUGUAAAAUAAAAAAUGGGUUAGUUAUUACUUCCAACAUACAGUGAGGGUACAGGCACUGGGUAAAUACUUCUUUUCCAAAAGGGAGAAAUUAGCCAAAAGAAAGGGGCUACAGGCCCCAUGUAAGUUUGAAACCCAGCAAGGGAGUCAUUAAAUCUUAAAGCUCCAAAUAAUCUCCUUUGAUUCCACAUCUCACUUCCAGGGCACACUGGGGCAAGGGGUGGGCUCCUAAGGUUGGGAAGCUGCACCUCUGAGGCUUUGCAAAGUAAAGCCCCUGAGGCUGCUUUCAUGGGCUAGUGUUCAUGCACCUGCGGCUUUUACAUGUGCAUGGUACAAGCUCCUGGUUGAUCUACCAUUCUGCAGUCUCGAAGACAAUGGCCCUCUUCUCACAGCUCCACUAGGUAGUGCCCCAGUGGGGCUCUGUGUGAGGGAUUCAACCCCAGAUUUCCCUUCAGUACUGCCCUAGUAGAGAUUCUCCAUGACGGCUCUGCUCCUGCAGCAGGGUUCUGCCUAGACAUUUAGGCUUUUCUACACAUACUCUGAAAUCUAGGCAGAGGCUCCCGAAGCCUUAACUCUUGCACUCUGAACAUUGGCAGGCUAAACACCUCAUAGAAACACCAAGUUUUAUGGCUUGCACAUUCUGAAGCAGCAGCCUGAGCUGUAUCUGAAGUCCUUUCAGCCACCCCUGGAGGCAGAGGGGUCAGGAUAUGGGGAGCAGUGUCUUGAGCCUGUGCAGGGAAGUGGGACCCUGGUCCCUGUUCAUGAAACCAUUCUUCCUUCUUAGACCUACAUGCCUGUGAUGGAAGGAACUGCUGCAAAGGUUUCUGAAAUGCUUUGAAAGUCUUUUCCCCUUUGUCUUGGCCAUCAGCAUUUGACUAUUCUUUACUUAUGCAAAUUUCUGUAGCUGGCUUGAACUCCUCCUCCAAAAAGGCCUUUUCUUUUCUACCACAUGGCCAGCCUUCAAAUUUUUCAAACUCGUACACUUUGCUUCCCUUUUAAAUAUAAGUUUCAGUUUCAGGUCAUUUCUUUGCUCACGCAUAUGAACAUAGGUUGUUAGAAGCAGCAGGCUAUAUCUUGACUGCUUUGCUGCUUAGAAAUUUCUCCUGUCAGUAACCUAAACCAUCACUCUCAAGUUCAAAGUUCCACAUACCCCUAGAUGCCUCCAGGCUCUUUGUUAAUGCAUAACAAAAAUGACCUUUACACUAGUUCCCAAGAAGUUCCUCAUUUUCAUCUGAGACCUUCUUAGCUGGGAUUUCAUUGUCCAUAUCACUAUCAGGAUUUUCAAAGCAACCGUUCAACAAGUCUCUAGGAAGUUACAAAUUUUCCUCAUCUUCCUGUCUUUUUCUCAGCCCUCCAAAUUGGUCCAACCUCUACCUGUUACCCAGUUCCAAAUGCAAAUUCACAUUUUCAGGUAUCUUUAUACCAAUGCCCCUGUCCUUGUUACCAAUUUUCCAUAUUAGUUCAUUCUUGCACUGCUAUAAAGAAAUACCUGAGACUGAGUGAUUUAUAAGGAAAAGAGGUUUAAUUGACUCACAAUUCUACAGGUGUACAGGAAGCAUGGCUAGGGAGGCCUCAGGAAACUUACAAGCAUGGUGGAAGGCAAAGGGGAAGCAGGCAUGUCUACAUGGCCAGAGCCAGGAGGAAGAGAGAGAGGUGGGAAGUGCCACAGACUUUUUAAAUAACCAGAUCUAGUGAGAGCUCUAUCAUGAAAACAAUACCAAAGGGGGAAAUCCACCCCCAUGAUCCAGUCACCUCCCACCAGGUCCCACCUCCAACACUGGGGAAUCACAACUUGGCAUGAGAUUUGGGCAGGGAUGCAAAUCCAAAUUAUAUCACAGUUCUUUCUGGAACGUUGCUCAUGUAGCUUCCUACAUAUGUGCAACUAUCCUCCUCUUUUUCUCCUCAUACCUGCCUACCCCCUCUGUUCAUAUUCCCCUCUCAAAAUCUCUUUCUGUUUUUCUUUUCUUAGUGACUUUCAAGAUGUCCUUUUAACUAGGAAUAGAACCUGUCAGAUAUGCUAACAUAACUGUAUCUGCUUUCAAAUUGUGUGACCUCUUGUUGAUGGUGAGCAACAUAUUUUCAACUUCUGUGAGUGACAGUAGAGUAAAAUUCUGAUGAGCUGAAGUCAGACUACGCAUUUUUGGAAAGCAGCUAAACCUCUUUGAGCCUCCAGGAAGACGUCCUCUCUCUAUCAAAUGCGGACUUUUAGAAAUAAUACUCUCUCAGCCACGUAUGCCACCCAGUAUUAUUAUCACGUGCCAUUACUGUUUGGUAGUUAUUUAUGUUCAUGUCAUCUUGGCUAGAUUGUGAACUUUUAAAAGGCAAGCCUUCUGCCUUUUACCUUUAUAUUCCCAUGCAUGCUUUGUAUGCUUAAGUGGUUAGCCACUUAAUAUAUUUUAAAAGAGAUAAUGUAUCCAUGUUAUUGAGUUAAAAUAAUCCAUGGAAGGCAUCUAUUACAAUGAUUGGCAUAUAGUAGAUAUUUAGUCAGUUAUAUUAGAGCACUCAGUCAAUAUGGGGAAUUUUGCUUCAUUUCCUCCUCUUUAAUUGAUUCUCCCAUUUCACAUACAUUGUCCUUCGGCUGAUUUUAGGAGCCUAUUUAUUUAUCUGCCUAUUUUUCAUUUUGAAGUAUUUUUUUUGACUUUCAAAGAAGACACAAGAAUAGCAUAAGGAAAUCCCACAUUCCAUGGAUGUAUGCUUAGUAUAUUGUAUCAAGGAGGCACAAAACAUCCCUUUACUGGUGGUGUUAAUUUUGAUCAUUUGAUUAAGGUGGCAUCUGUCAGAUCUUUCUACCAUAAAGAUGCUAUAUUUCAUGCUGUUAAUAGAGAAAAACCCUAGGCUGGGUAAUUAUAAAGGAAAGAGGUUUAAUUGACUCACAGUUCCAUAUGGCGGGGGAAGCCUCACAAUCAUGGCAGAAAGCAAAUGAGGAGCAAAGUCACAUCUUACAUGGCAGCGGGCAAAGAGAGCAUGUGCAGGGGAACUCCCCUUUGUAAAACCAGCGGAUCCCAUGAGACUUAUUCACUAUCAUGACAAAAGCACAAGAAAGAUCCACCCCCCAUGAUUCAGUUACCUACCAUCAGGUCCCUCCCACAACGUGUGAGAAUUAUGGGAGCUACAAUUCAAGAUGAGAUUUGAGUGGGGACACAGCCAAACCAUAUCAGAUACUUUUUUUUUUUUUUGAGACGGAAUCUUGCUCUGUCGCCCAGGCUGGGGUGCAGUGGCACGAUCUCAGCUCACUGCAACCUCUACCUCCCGGGUUCAAGCGAUUCUUCUGCCUCAGCCUCCUGAGUAGCUGGGACUACAGGCUCCCACCACCACACCCAGAUAAUUUUUGUGUUUUUAGUAGAGACAGGGUUUCACCAUAUUGGCCAGGCUUGUCUCGAACUCCUGAACUUGUGAUCCGCCUGCCUUGGCCUCCCAAAGUGCUGAGAUUAGAGGUGUGAGCUGCUGCGCCUGGCCCAGAUACUAUGUUUUUCCAUUGUAGUUCAUAAGUGUCUGGUGGGGAAAUACUGUAAAUAUCUUGCUUCUCAUCACAUUUUUACUAAGUUUAGCCCAGUUUAGCCAGUUUAUUAAGUUUAACAGUCCAUUGAUGAUUGUUUCCUGAAACAAAUUAUCAUACAGUUUACCAUGUAGUGACUUUUCUAUUCACAUCAUUCCUUCUAUAUCUAUUAGUUAGCAUUUUACCAUAAUAAAGAGUUUUUCUUUCCUCUUCAUUUAGCUUUGUAUUCAUUUGUUAACUUACAUUAGUAUAGACUCAUGGAAUCUUAUUUUGUUAAAUUGAUUAUGCAUCAAAAUCAUCAUUUUGUUUAUUUGUUUUUUUUUCUUAAAUUGUGCAGAUGGUAAAAUUGGAUGGGUGGCAGAGAUGGCUUUGAGUACUCUUGUUUCAGUUUGGGGGUGUGCCAAACAGCAGGCCCAGAGGAUAAGCAUUCAUGUGGUUUACACCAGUUUAACAAGGACCAACAUGAAAGAGAAAAUAGUUGUAGAUUACUCUGAAAUAUAUUGUUUCCUCUGUGUUUCAGGAAAUAAAAAGGGUCAGUUGGAGGUAGUUUAGUCACUAAGGCCACUGCAACUUCCUCUCUUAACUCUUAGCAGCUGGAGAUGUUUUGCUGUAGACACACAGUUUGAACAUAAAAGGGACUUCAGUACUAGUGCUAAUAACAUCCAGAUUGAUAAAACCAAGCCUUUGUGGCACAACUAUUUCUUAUGUGGACUUAAAGGAAUUCAGGAACACUUUGGUCUUAGUAACCUGACUGGAAUGAACUGCCUGGUAGAUGGAAAUAUCCCACCAAGUUCUGGCCUCUCCAGCUCCAGUGCUUUGGUCUGUUGUGCUGGCUUGGUGACGCUCACAGUGCUGGGAAGGAAUCUAUCCAAGGUGGAACUUGCAGAAAUCUGUGCCAAGAGUGAGCGUUACAUUGGCACUGAAGGAGGAGGCAUGGACCAGUCUAUAUCAUUUCUUGCAGAAGAAGGAACUGCCAAGUUGAUAGAAUUUAGUCCUCUGAGGGCAACCGAUGUAAAACUCCCAAGUGGAGCAGUGUUUGUGAUUGCCAACAGUUGUGUGGAGAUGAAUAAGGCAGCAACUUCCCAUUUCAAUAUCAGGGUGAUGGAGUGUCGGCUGGCUGCGAAGCUCCUGGCUAAAUACAAAAGCUUGCAAUGGGACAAAGUACUGAGGCUGGAGGAGGUGCAGGCUAAACUAGGGAUUAGUCUAGAAGAAAUGCUGUUGGUCACAGAAGAUGCCCUUCAUCCUGAACCCUAUAACCCUGAGGAGAUCUGCAGGUGUCUGGGAAUUAGCCUGGAGGAACUCCGAACCCAAAUCCUGAGUCCAAACACUCAAGAUGGGAUCAUACUGCACAUCCCUCAGUGCUGUGAUGAGAACUUUAUGAGGUUCAAGCAAUUCUCCCACUUCAGUCUCUCAAAUAGCUGGGAUUACAUGCACCCACCAUCAUCAUGCCCAGUGCUCAUCUUCAAACUCUAUCAGCGGGCAAAGCAUGUGUACAGCGAGGCUGCGCGAGUGCUCCAGUUUAAGAAGAUAUGUGAAGAAGCACCUGAAAACAUGGUCCAGCUGCUGGGAGAGUUGAUGAACCAGAGCCACAUGAGCUGCCGGGACAUGUAUGAGUGCAGCUGCCCCGAGCUGGAUCAGCUGGUGGACAUCUGUCGGAAGUUUGGGGCUCAAGGGUCACGACUUACUGGAGCAGGAUGGGGAGGCUGCACAGUAUCAAUGGUACCUGCGGACAAGCUGCCCAGCUUUCUAGCAAAUGUGCACAAAGCUUAUUACCAGAGGAGUGAUGGAAGCUUAGCACCGGAGAAGCAAAGUUUGUUUGCUACCAAACCUGGAGGUGCUUUGGAAAUACCAGCCAGCUCAUGCAUCUUAAGAUAAUAUAAAAUCAAUGGACUCUGACCUCCAAAAUUGAAGAGAACACGAUUAAACUCUGGACCAGUACUACUAUAGUGCGACUGUAAGAGGAAGAAAAUAAUCAAGACAACGAUUACUUUUGUGUUUCUAAAAAACUGUGAAUAAAAUAUAACUUCAUAUUUAGCAUAAAGUUACCAUUUGAUAUAUUAAAAUAAAGGAAAUUCUACAAAGCA